CCACCCGCCGCUGUGUCCAGACAGAGAAUGUUCUAACGCUGGGGGCGGCUGCGGAUGAAGUCCUUGGGGAGAAAAGGAGCAGGCCAAGGGCGAUGGUGGAGUAGAGCUGCCUCUCAGAGGCAGCAUGAGCUGAGAGGGUGAUAGGAAGGCGGCGCUAGACAGCAUGGAGGACUUUCUGCUCUCCAAUGGGUACCAGCUGGGCAAGACCAUUGGGGAAGGGACCUACUCAAAAGUCAAAGAAGCAUUUUCCAAAAAACACCAAAGAAAAGUGGCAAUUAAAGUUAUAGACAAGAUGGGAGGGCCAGAAGAGUUUAUCCAGAGAUUCCUCCCUCGGGAGCUCCAAAUCGUCCGUACCCUGGACCACAAGAACAUCAUCCAGGUGUAUGAGAUGCUGGAGUCUGCCGACGGGAAAAUCUGCCUGGUGAUGGAGCUCGCUGAGGGAGGGGAUGUCUUUGACUGCGUGCUGAAUGGGGGGCCACUGCCUGAAAGCCGGGCCAAGGCCCUCUUCCGUCAGAUGGUUGAGGCCAUCCGCUACUGCCAUGGCUGUGGUGUGGCCCACCGGGACCUCAAAUGUGAGAACGCCUUGUUGCAGGGCUUCAACCUGAAGCUGACUGACUUUGGCUUUGCCAAGGUGUUGCCCAAGUCACACCGGGAGCUGAGCCAGACCUUCUGCGGCAGUACAGCCUAUGCUGCCCCCGAGGUGCUGCAGGGCAUUCCCCACGAUAGCAAAAAAGGUGAUGUCUGGAGCAUGGGUGUGGUCCUGUAUGUCAUGCUCUGUGCCAGCCUACCUUUUGACGACACAGACAUCCCCAAGAUGCUGUGGCAGCAGCAGAAGGGGGUGUCCUUCCCCACUCAUCUGAGCAUCUCGGCCGAUUGCCAGGACCUGCUCAAGAGGCUCCUGGAACCCGAUAUGAUCCUCCGGCCUUCAAUUGAAGAAGUUAGUUGGCAUCCAUGGCUAGCAAGCACUUGAUAAAAGCAAUGGCAAGUGCUCUCCAAUAAAGUAGGGGGAGAAAGCAAACCCAAAAA